CGUUGCCUUGGCUACACCGUCUGUUAGGGCCGCGCACGAGAUCAGUAACUGAGACCUCACCGCGUUGACCCAGCACCAGGGCUCGCGGGGGUCCCGCGAGGGUCUCGGUAGCCGCGCGCCCAGAGACCCCCGCCGCGGCCCGAUUCUCUGAGCGCCAGACAUGAACCGCAAGAAACUGCAGAAGCUGACGGACACCUUAACCAAAAAUUGCAAGCAUUGUCCAAGUUCUGGAAGCUUACCAAGAGACCCAUAGGAGAAAACGGUGCUCAACUUCUCAACAUCUUUCGGAGAGAUGAGUUGUGUCAUCUCAUCUGUGCCUCAGAACAAUAUUUGUUUGGAAACCAGAGUUCAGCACAACUAAACACGUGCUGAGAUGGAAAAAUGGCUAACCAACAUCCCCUCUGCUACCAUUUUAUGUACAUGAACAGAGUACAUCAUUCUUCAUGCAGGCUUUUCUUCCGCAACAACUAACAGCUCUUGCUUUUUAGGAGUUAAUAAAUUUGAAGUGAACUGUCUUAUAAAGCUUUUUUAUGACUUGGUGGGAGGAGUAGAGAGGCAAGGUCUGGUUGUUGGACUGGAUCGUAAUGCAUUUCGAAACAUCCUGCAUGUGACAUUUGGAAUGACAGAUGACAUGAUUAUGGACAGAGUAUUCCGAGGUUUUGAUAAAGAUAAUGAUGGCUGUGUAAAUGUAUUGGAGUGGAUUCAUGGAUUAUCACUGUUUCUUCGAGGAUCUUUGGAAGAAAAAAUGAAAUAUUGCUUUGAAGUGUUUGAUUUGAAUGGUGACGGAUUCAUUUCAAAGGAGGAAAUGUUUCACAUGUUGAAGAACAGCCUUCUCAAACAGCCAUCUGAGGAAGACCCUGAUGAAGGAAUUAAAGAUUUGGUUGAAAUAACACUGAAGAAAAUGGAUCAUGACCAUGAUGGGAAGCUGUCUUUUGCAGACUAUGAACUGGCUGUGAGAGAAGAGACUCUUCUACUGGAGGCCUUUGGGCCAUGUCUUCCUGAUCCAAAGAGCCAGAUGGAAUUUGAAGCUCAAGUAUUCAAAGAUCCAAAUGAAUUCAAUGAUAUGUGAAUAACUAAAUGUCUAUAUUGUCUCAAGUGAGUAAAAAAGGAGGCACACACAUAUUGCUUAUUUUUUCUACUUAGUUCAGAAAAAUGAUGUUGAAUUGUGUGUUUCAGGGUGAAGAUGAGGUUCACUUACAUAUAUCAUUUAACAUCAGUGUAAGAUGCAAUUAAAAUAGAUGGAAGACAAGAAGUCCCUUAUUAGAUGAUGGGUUUGGCAAGACAGUUAACUUUUCUACAGAUGUUUUAUCACAUAGACUAUCUGUCGAAGCACAUAACUGGCAUAAAACCUUUGGGUUCAUUAAAUGAAUAGAGAGAUUACAUAAUUAUGAAUUGUUAAUACAAAUAUUCUGCAUGUCAAAAAGAAGCUGGGUGUACACUGAAAAAUCAUUGAAACUACUGGAUUUCCUUUGAAACAAAUAAUGAAGAUGGCAUCAAAAGAAUAAGAGUAUUCUAUUGAGCAUUGAAACGCCUUUCUGGUAGGCAUUGAGGGAGAUCUAGAGAGAUGAAAGAUACAUGGAAAUCAUAUUAUAUUGAAAUAUAAUAUGAUUUGCAUUAUUGUUUGAGGCUUUGGCUAAAUAACGUUACUGAUUGUAAGCACCUGAAGGCAAGGGUUUUAUCCACCACAUCUUUGUCUGCCAUAGCAUUUAGUCCUCUGCAUACAAUGGGCUGUCCAUAAUUACUGUAGAUUGGACUGAAAAUCAAAAAGUACCACAAGAUAAAUGCAAACUCUUGGUGAGCAGAGGGAGAACAUGUACUGAGUUUCUUAGGUUUCAUGGCUAAUGCAUUGGCACAGCUUUCAGUGUAUCCCUGCAGUCCUUCCAGAUAGUCCCUGCCCCAUGCAUUGCAGAUGGUUGCCAAAGCCCCCCUCUGUCCUGGCACCCAGUGUUCCUCCAUCCUGACUCCACGUAUUGCCCCCUUGCCACUGCCUGAGUGCACCAUAGUGUCCCCAUCCCCCCACUGCCUGGAGUUCCCCUUGUGUACCCCCUUAUCAGGGCACGACCUAACUGUGCCCUGCUGGCUGUGACCUCCUGAAGACAGACCUGGCUUCUCCCUGCAUCCAGUUCCCCAGUAUGUGCUGUGGGCAUCCUGAGAAGCCUGAAAAAGACAGGGCCAGGUUAGGCUUGGGUGAGCUGCUUUCUGCCUUCUUGGUACACACAGUAAGCAGUGGAGAGGCGUGUUACACCGUAUCUGUUCUAUCCUCAUCUAAAUACUGAGAGGCUAGUUGGGAUAGUAAAUCUUUCUUACUACAUAUGCAUUAAGUUUAAGUAAAAUAGAAUAUUGUGUGAAAAAAUGCACUGUUACUAAUAAAUGGAAUAAACAGAUCCAUGAAAUAAAAGAAAACAUAUUUUACUGUCCAA